AGAGUUGACUUCCGGCGGCUUGUGGGAGUGCUGGUUCUGUCCUCCUUGCGGGUGCGGAGAUGGUUGUCUUGGUUACGGGUCCUAACGGUCCCCUGCCUUGAAAUCCCUUGUUGAGGGCCUGCAACCUUGUGCUUCCGACCGGAGACGCCUUUGGUCCCUCGGUGUCUGCACUGGCUGCUGGUCAAGGCUUCAGUGUGGAGUAAUUGACACUUUCGAGAAUAUUAAAAUCAAAUUAGAGAAGAAAACUGAUCCAUAAUAAUAAAAAUGUCUCGAAAAAUUUCAAAGGAGUCAAAAAAAGUGAACAUCUCUAGUUCUCUGGAAUCUGAAGAUAUUAGUUUAGAAACAACAGUUCCUACGGAUGAUAUUUCCUCAUCAGAAGAGCGAGAGGGCAAAGUCAGAAUCACCAGGCAGCUAAUUGAACGAAAAGAACUACUUCAUAAUAUUCAGUUACUAAAAAUUGAGCUAUCCCAGAAAACUAUGAUGAUCGACAAUUUGAAAGUGGAUUAUCUUACAAAGAUUGAAGAAUUGGAGGAGAAACUUAAUGAUGCACUUCACCAGAAGCAGCUACUAACAUUGAGAUUAGACAACCAAUUGGCUUUUCAACAGAAAGAUGCCAGCAAAUAUCAAGAAUUAAUGAAACAAGAAAUGGAAACCAUUUUGUUGAGACAGAAACAACUAGAAGAGACAAAUCUUCAGCUAAGAGAAAAAGCUGGAGAUGUUCGUCGAAACCUGCGUGACUUUGAGUUGACAGAAGAGCAAUAUAUUAAAUUAAAAGCUUUUCCUGAAGAUCAGCUUUCUAUUCCUGAAUAUGUAUCUGUUCGCUUCUAUGAGCUAGUGAAUCCAUUAAGAAAGGAAAUCUGUGAACUACAAGUGAAAAAGAAUAUCCUAGCAGAAGAAUUAAGUACAAACAAAAACCAACUGAAGCAGCUGACAGAGACAUAUGAGGAAGAUCGAAAAAACUACUCUGAAGUUCAAAUUAGAUGUCAACGUUUGGCCUUAGAAUUAGCAGACACAAAACAGUUAAUUCAGCAAGGUGACUACCGUCAAGAGAACUAUGAUAAAGUCAAGAGUGAACGUGAUGCACUUGAACAGGAAGUAAUUGAGCUUAGGAGAAAACAUGAAAUACUUGAAGCCUCUCACAUGAUUCAAACAAAAGAACGAAGUGAAUUAUCAAAAGAGGUAGUCACCUUAGAGCAAACUGUUACUUUACUGCAAAAGGAUAAAGAAUAUCUUAAUCGCCAAAACAUGGAGCUUAGUGUUCGCUGUGCUCAUGAAGAGGAUCGCCUUGAAAGACUUCAAGCUCAACUGGAAGAAAGCAAAAAGGCUAGAGAAGAGAUGUAUGAAAAAUAUGUAGCAUCCAGAGACCAUUAUAAAACAGAAUAUGAAAAUAAACUACAUGAUGAACUAGAACAAAUCAGAUUGAAAACCAACCAAGAAAUUGAUCAACUUCGAAAUGCCUCUAGGGAAAUGUAUGAACGAGAAAACAGGUCUGGAGGCUGGGAAGUCCAAUAUCUACGUACUGGCAUCUGGCAAGAGCCUUCUCACUACAUUAUCAUAUGGCAUAAGGCAAGAAGAAAUCUCCGAGAAGCAAGGGAUAAUGCUGUGGCUGAAAAGGAACGAGCAGUGAUGGCUGAAAAGGAUGCUUUAGAAAAACACGAUCAGCUCUUAGACAGGUACAGAGAACUACAACUUAGUACAGAAAGCAAAGUAACAGAAUUUCUCCAUCAAAGUAAAUUAAAAUCUUUUGAAAGUGAGCGUGUUCAACUUCUGCAAGAGGAAACAGCAAGAAAUCUCACACAGUGUCAAUUGGAAUGUGAAAAAUAUCAGAAAAAAUUGGAGGUUUUAACCAAAGAAUUUUAUAGUCUCCAAGCCUCUUCUGAAAAACGCAUUACUGAACUUCAAGCACAGAACUCAGAGCAUCAAGCAAGGCUAGACAUUUAUGAGAAACUGGAAAAAGAGCUUGAUGAAAUAAUAAUGCAAACUGCAGAAAUUGAAAAUGAAGAUGAGGCUGAAAGGGUUCUUUUUUCCUACGGCUAUGGUGCUAAUGUUCCCACAACAGCCAAAAGACGACUAAAGCAAAGUGUUCACUUGGCAAGAAGAGUGCUUCAAUUAGAAAAACAAAACUCGCUGAUUUUAAAAGAUCUGGAACAUCGAAAGGACCAAGUAACACAGCUUUCACAAGAGUAGUUGAAAGAUACUGCUUCACUCCCUUCUAGUUUGCAUCGUUUCUGCCAAGAUAUUGCCGUCAUCCUUAUCUUUGUUCCUCUCUAGGUAAUGUGUAUUUCUUUAGCUGCUUUUAAGAGAUUUUUAGUCACUGGCUGUAAGCAAUUUGAUUAUCAUUUGGCUUUCUGGAGUUUUCUUCAUGUUUCCUAUGCUUGGGUUUUGUUGAACAUCUUACAUAUGUGAGUUUAUCAAAUUUAUAAAUUUCUUAAAUUUUUAAAUACUUCAAUCCUCUCACCUUCCUUUGAGGACUUCAAUGAGAUAUAUAUUAGGUUGCUUAAAGUUAUUCUACAACAGAACAAAUGAUGUUCUCUUCAGUUUUUUUCAGUCUUUUUUCUGCUUUUCUUUUGAAUAGCUUCUUUUACUGUGUCUUCCAGUUCACUAAUCUUUUUUUCACCACUGUAUAAUCUGCUUUCAGUUCAAUCCAGUUUUUAUCUCAGAUAUUGUAGUUUUCAUUUCUAGAAGUUCAAAUUGGAUCUUCUUUGUGUCUUUUAGGUCUCUCCUUAACAUUCUCAAACUUUAUUUUCUGGAAUAUGUGAAAUAUAAUUUCAAUAACUUUUUUAUAUUCUUGCCUACUAAUUCUAUUAUUUUGUCAUUUCAUGGCUGCCUUCAAUAAAUUUGAAUUUUCUCAUUAUAUAUCACAUUGUUCAGCUUCUUUGCAUAUGUAGUAAUUAUUUACUGGAUGCCAGACCUUGUAAAUUUUACCUUGAUGCUAUAUAUUUUGUAUUCCUAUAUGUUUUUGUUAGCUUUGUUCUGGGACAUAGUUAGGUUUCUUGGAAACAGUUUGAUUCUUCCAAAUCUUGCUUUUAAGCUUUUUUAGGCAGAGAAGGGUUUAUCGUAAGGCCAAUUUCUCCCCCAUUACUACAACCAAACUCUUUGAGUAUUCCAUGUCCUGUAAAUUGUAAGGUUUUCUACUUUGGCUGAUGGAAAUAAGCACUAUGCCUUGCCCAUGUUCACUUCAGAGAUUGCUCCUACCAAUCUUGUCUGUAGUUCUGUCUCCUGUCUUUAUACAUAUGCACUGUUCUGUGCCAGGUAAAUACUUAAGGGGCACUAUCUGUAAAUUGUCAGAGUUCUGUCUCUUUGCAGCUCCCUUUUCUUCAGUAGUCUCCCAUAUGAACUGUAACCACCUUGGUUAUUACUUCUAUCAACAGCUCCUUAACUCAGGGAAUUUGACAGGCUCUGCCUUAAUUCUCCUUCCCAGCACCACAGCUUGAAAGCUGUCUCUAGUCAAUAAACUAAGGCAGUCAUAGAGUUUACCUUGUUUGUUUCCUGUGUGUCAGGGAUCUCCUUCAUUGCAUGAUGUCCAAUGUCUUUCGACCGUUGUUUUAUUAGUUGGUCCAGUAUAACAGAGAAAACAAGUUAUUCUUUUUUGUGUAUUUGUGUAUACCCACUAAUUCUCAAGAAACUGCCAAGUUUAGUUAAGAGUCAAGUGUCAGUGUGGAGUUUGUUAAACAGUAGAAAAUCCAGAAUCAUAAAGUGUGCCACAUUACUGCCAACAGUAAGGCAGCUAAGAAUUGGUCUUUCUUAGCUGCCUCAAACCUUGAUAUAUGCUCUCCUUCUAGUUAUUCAGUAAAUAUUUAUCAAUUUCCCACUAUAUUCAACAACUGAUGACAAAAUAGACAUGGUUUUUCACUUCUAACAUAACCAACCUUAUUCACAAAGGCCUUAUUUUCUACUGUAAGCACGCAGAGAUUUAUCUUUUACAACUGACUUAAUUUCAGGAAGCUUGUCUAGAAAGUGGGACAUGCACAGUCAUCAGUAACCACAUGGCAAGGUUUAGCUACCUGGAAUUUUGUACCUAGAAGGCAUUGCUAGAUUUGAAAGAGGCGUCAAGGUGCAUAGGUAAAAUAAAGUAGACCUAUAUGUAUUAACUUUGAAAGAAAUUUAUACUGUAUUGAUGAUUUUUCAAAAAACAAAUUGCAGAAUAAUUUCUGUUUCUCUGUUUGGGUUUUAAUAUAUUUGUGUGUGUGCAUGUACCCAGCAUAUACAGAGAGGAUGGGAUUGUGUUUCUGUUUAAACAUACAGAAAAUGAAAAAAAUCUGAAAAUAUGUCAUGCAAAGGGGACACAAAUACCACUAGUCAUGGAUUAGCAAUAUGAAAUGAGCUUUAUUGGUAUAAAGUAAGUACUUGAAGUAAUAAAACAUUUAUCUCUGC